ACUGAGCCAGGGAGCACGGAAGUUGUGCCACUGUGCAACUUGGGUUUUCUUUAUCCUGCAGUCUUUACCUCAGCAGAACCGCACACCACAGACUCCCUCCAGCUCUUUGUGUGUGGCUCUCUCAGGGUCCAACAAGAGCAAGCUGUGGGUCUGUGAGUGUUUAUGUGUGCUUUUAUUCACUUCACACUUAUUGAAAAGUGUGUAUGUGAGAGGGUGGGGUGUGUGUGUCAAAGAGAGUGAGGAAGAGAAGGAGAGAGAGAUCAAUUGAUUCUGCAGCCUCAGCUCCAGCAUCCCUCAGUUGGGAGCUUCCAAAGCCGGGUGAUCACUUGGGGUGCAUAGCUCGGAGAUGCAGUCCCCCUGGAAAAUCCUUACGGUGGCGCCUCUAUUCUUGCUCCUGUCUCUUCAGUCCUCGGCCUCUCCAGCCAACGAUGACCAGUCCAGGCCCAGCCUCUCGAAUGGGCACACCUGUGUAGGGUGUGUGCUGGUGGUGUCUGUAAUAGAACAGCUUGCUCAAGUUCACAACUCGACGGUCCAGGCCUCGAUGGAGAGACUGUGCAGCUACCUGCCUGAAAAACUGUUCUUGAAAACCACCUGCUAUUUAGUCAUUGACAAGUUUGGAUCAGACAUCAUAAAACUGCUUAGCGCAGAUAUGAAUGCUGAUGUGGUAUGUCACACUCUGGAGUUUUGUAAACAGAACACUGGCCAACCAUUGUGUCAUCUCUACCCUCUUCCCAAGGAGACAUGGAAAUUUACACUACAGAAGGCAAGACAAAUUGUCAAGAAGUCCCCGAUUCUGAAAUAUUCUAGAAGUGGUUCUGACAUUUGUUCACUCCCGGUUUUGGCCAAGAUCUGCCAGAAAAUUAAAUUAGCUAUGGAACAGUCUGUGCCAUUCAAAGAUGUGGAUUCAGACAAAUACAGCGUUUUCCCAACACUGCGGGGCUAUCACUGGCGGGGGAGAGACUGUAAUGACAGCGACGAGUCAGUGUACCCAGGUAGAAGGCCGAACAACUGGGAUGUCCAUCAGGAUUCAAACUGUAAUGGCAUUUGGGGUGUCGAUCCAAAAGAUGGAGUUCCAUAUGAGAAGAAAUUCUGUGAAGGUUCACAGCCCAGGGGAAUCAUUUUGCUGGGAGACUCAGCUGGGGCUCAUUUUCACAUCUCUCCUGAAUGGAUCACAGCGUCGCAGAUGUCUUUGAACUCUUUCAUCAAUCUACCAACAGCCCUUACCAACGAGCUUGACUGGCCCCAACUCUCUGGUGCUACAGGAUUUCUGGACUCCACUGUUGGAAUUAAAGAAAAAUCUAUUUACCUUCGCUUAUGGAAAAGAAACCACUGUAAUCACAGGGACUACCAGAAUAUUUCAAGAAAUGGUGCAUCUUCCCGAAACCUGAAGAAAUUUAUAGAAAGCUUGUCUAGAAACAAGGUGUUGGACUAUCCCGCCAUCGUUAUAUAUGCCAUGAUUGGAAAUGAUGUCUGCAGUGGGAAGAGUGACCCAGUCCCAGCCAUGACCACUCCUGAGAAACUCUACUCCAACGUCAUGCAGACUCUGAAGCAUCUAAAUUCCCACCUGCCCAAUGGCAGCCAUGUUAUUUUGUAUGGCUUACCAGAUGGAACCUUUCUCUGGGAUAAUUUGCACAACAGAUAUCAUCCUCUCGAAGGUGAAAUGUAAAAUGAGCUGAGGAAGCCCAAACAGGAGACAGACCCGUGAGUCAAAGACAGGGAUUUCUCUGAACCUCAAUGGUAAGUGCUUCCUGGUGGCCUGUUAGAAUUCUCUAGAGCACAGUCCUCCAGCCUGCUCAUUUCCUGCUUCUACACUCUCUUGGGGUCCUUAGCUCCGAAAGGCUUUAAAAUGUCCCUGGAACCUUCUAAUGGCAACUCAAAUAUUCUCGAUACUGUACAAAUAACAUAAAAGUGCUAGUAAUUUGCAUUAGGAAGGUGUGAUCCUUAACCCUGUGAGAUAGAUGUUUUUAUCAACCACAAUAAUUUCAUUUUAUAGAUGAAAAAAACCAAGGCUCAGAGAGGUUAGAUAGCUUGCCAAAUGCCACAGAGCUCACUGAAUAUGUUGUAGCAGGGCUCUGCUUUCUGUAUUUCAGAGGAGAAUGUAUUUAUUAAGUGCCAACUAUGUGCCAGGCACUAUUCUAGGCACAGGGUAACCAGCAGAAAACACAAUAGUCCUAAGUUCCUGCCCACAGAAAGCUUAUAUUACAAUGGGAAAAUGACCCAAAAGUAUAUCAGAAGGUGAUAAGUGCCACAGGAAGAAAACUGAGCAAGGAAGAGGAACAGGGAGCUGGCCUCAGUCUUCCCUGAUGAGCAUCUAUAAGAAGAGGCCUGGGUACCUUCCUCUCAGCCCCAUAUUGACAGCACCUGCACCAAUCUAUCAUGAAGAAGGGACUAUCCCUUCCCUGGUGUUACCCCACUCACCUCCUGAGCCCAACCCACUAAAAGGUGCUGGCAGUCCAAGCACCUUCUUAGGAGUCAGGCGAGAAAUUCAAAGAAGACCUGAAACUCAUUCUUUCACGCCCUCCUUAGAGGGAGUGGGUGGGGAGCAAGAUUUCCCAUUUCAGGCCAUCAAGAGCCUUUUCUUGCAUAUACUACUUUGUGUGAAUCUUUCCAGUCUUCUCUUGUCCUCUUCCUGCAGUCCCUGUCUAAGACAAACACCCCACUUCUCCCUCAGGAAAUUCCGCCUCUCCCCACCUGGGAAAAGAGUAAGGGUCCUUUAGCUAGCUCUCAAAGGCUCUGGUCUCUUAGUUGGAGGGACAAUGGUGGACACCCACAUUCCCUAUUCUCCACCAAUAAGGAUGAAACCAUUUUCCUCUUGAGUUACUCAUGUAUCACAAAUAUUAUCAUCCAAGCAAAACACUGUACAGCCUCACCUAAGUAGAGCAUAUUCUUCCUGUUCAUGCAACUUUGACCACGCCGCCUUAGAAAUAACAUGAUCACACAUGGAACUUCACUCCAUUCUGGGCUGCUUUGCAUGCAGAAAGGACACCAACCUGGGCUAAGAAUGUCUCUUUGAACCACGGGAUAUGAAAAUUGUACAUCUGCCCUCAACUGAUUCUUUCAGAUUUCCAAAUGUGUCUCCUACACUAAGAAAUGCUUUGGAAAGAGAAGCUGAGGGCAGGGAAGUUUGUUCCCAAUUUACUCCAUCACAGUAAUAGCGACUUGACUUCCAUUUUUCUGAUUUCUAAUCCCAUUUUCUUUCCAUGAACUCUGGUUACGCCACCUCCAUAAAUUCUUUCCGAUAUGCCAUGCAAUUCACUUGAUUUAUGAGACAUGUUUGGUUUCAUAAAUAUGAGACCAAAGGUAAGAAUGACUCCAUGCAAUUUGGAAAGGACUAGGGGAAGGAAAAAUGUAUGUAAGAAUGUAAGAAUGAGGCCAGGCACGGUGGCUCAUGCCUGUAAUCUUAGCAAUUUGGGAGGCCGAGGUGGGUGGAUCAACUGUGGCGAGAGUUCAAGUCAAGCCUGGCCAACAUAGUGAAACCUCGUCUCUUCUAAAAAUACAAAAAUUAGCAGGGUGUGGUGGCACACACCUGUGAUCCCAACUACUCAGGAGACUGAAGCAGGAGAAUCGCUUGAACCCAGGAGGCAGAGGUUGCAGUGAGCCGAGAUCGCACCAUUGCACUCCAGCCUGGGUGACAAGAGUGAAAAACAAACAAACAAACAAAAACUCUGUCCAAAAAAAAAAAAAAAAAGAAUGUACGAAUGGUAUGUAAGCAUGACUCCACGCAAUUUGGAAAGGACUGAGGGAAGAAAAAAGGAUGAUUGGGGGAUUUGUCCACUUCUGUGGAUUCUCUAGGCCAGUGGUUCUCAACUGGGGGCAACCCACUCACCCCCACCCUGCUUUUAUCACAUCUGGAGAUAGAAGAGGGGUGCAACUAGGCUGGGUGCAGUGGCUCACGCCUGUAAUCUCAGCACUUUGGGAGGCCAAGGUGGGCGGAU